GUCUGUUUGCUGCGGUAGGAACAUGGCGGAUCGGCUCACGCAGCUUCAGGACGCUGUGAAUUCGCUUGCAGAUCAGUUUUGUAAUGCCAUUGGAGUAUUGCAGCAAUGUGGUCCUCCUGCCUCUUUCAAUAAUAUUCAGACAGCAAUUAACAAAGACCAGCCAGCUAACCCUACAGAAGAGUAUGCCCAGCUUUUUGCAGCACUGAUUGCACGAACAGCAAAAGACAUUGAUGUUUUGAUAGAUUCCUUACCCAGUGAAGAAUCUACAGCUGCUUUACAGGCUGCUAGCUUGUAUAAGCUAGAAGAAGAAAACCAUGAAGCUGCUACAUGUCUGGAGGAUGUUGUUUAUCGAGGAGACAUGCUUCUGGAGAAGAUACAAAGCGCACUUGCUGAUAUUGCACAGUCACAGCUGAAGACAAGAAGUGGUACCCAUAGCCAGUCUCUUCCAGACUCAUAGCAUCAGUGGAUACCAUGUGGCUGAGAAAAGAACUGUUUGAGUGCCAUUAAGAAUUCUGCAUCAGACUUAGAUACAAGCCUUACCAACAAUUACAGAAACAUUAAACACUAUGACACAUUACCUUUUUAGCUAUUUUUAAUAGUCUUCUAUUUUCACUCUUGAUAAGCUUAUAAAAUCAUGAUUGAAUCAGCUUUAAAGCAUCAUACCAUCAUUUUUUAACUGAGUGAAAUUAUUAAGGCAUGUAAUACAUUAAUGAACAUAAUAUAAGGAAACAUAUGUAAAAUUCUGUUAUGACAUAAUUUAUGUCUCCAUUUUGUUGUAUUGGCCAGUACUUUUACAAAUCAAAACAUCUCUCAAGCCAAAGGAGAAGACAGUAAGAACAGACAUAAGGGACAUUUUAGUUUGGGCUAGUGUCCUGCCUCUUAGAGGUGGCAUUGUGUAAAUCUGAGCUUUGAGCAAGAAAGUUUUGGAAAUUGUGUUGCUUUUAAGAAAUAGAGUUAGUGUGGCUGGAUAAGAAAGUCACAUUUAUGCAAAUGUUUCUUCUGCUAGAACCUCAUACCUGUUCUAGUUCAUCUCCACGUUUAUUUUACCAAGAGAUCCUCUGUCAAGAGAAUUUCCUGGCUGUUGUGAAAGAAUUUUUCUACAUCCUGAACUAUUUUUCCUAUUUCUUUUCACCUUGCUUUUUUUCAUCCUUAAUUUGCUUGUCAUCACAAUGAAGUAUGUUUUUUGAAUCAUCAAUUCUUUCUCAUUCUCCAUUUAUCUGAAGGUUCUUUUGCCCUUAUUAACCUCUCAACUUUUAUUGCUGUAUUCUAGUCAGACCAGAACAUACUUCCACUACAUCAGUUACUUGGCAUCAUUUCACCUCAGUUUAUUAUUGCCAAAUAAUAAUUUGUGUCAGCAUUUUCAACUAUGGUUAUUCAUCCAACCCUUGGAUCUCUUUGAGUCUACUGAUAAUCUCCACUGGAAAGGUGGAAUUGAAAUGUGGUCCACAUUUUAACUAGCUAUUUCCUGGGGCUGUAUUUUUCAGAAUAUGCUGAGCUACAUUUGCUGCAAUCUGUUGCUAUUCAGAGUUUAAGUUUCAGGAGAAAACAGGAACAAUAGAACACUCUGCCUGUUAUUUUUGUUGUAAUCAAGCUUUUCCACAGUUCUUGAAAAGUACUAUGUUUCAAAUUUCAGGAACACCAGCGUUAGCUGUAAAAGUUGCAGCAAUUUAUUGGCUAGUCAUAGAAAAUUUUUGAACUUUUAACUGUAUUUUAAUUGAUGUUUAUUAAAAACACUUUGCUAUCAGAUAUUUGGCAUAAAUCUGUACUCUUCAUUAUAGUUUUGGGGGGAGAGAAGAUUCAGUCAGAAAACUUAUUCAAAGUACCUAAGUAUUAUAAAGGAGUCAAAAAGGUACAAAGAGAAAAGGUCAAGACAUUUUUCAAAUGAGGGAAAACUAACAGGAUUUAUCACUAGUAAACCUGCUCUAAAAGAAUUCAAGGGAAGCUUUUUAAAAAGAAGGGAAGUUAUAGCAGAAGGAAACUUAGAAUGGCAGGAAUAAAGAAGGCAUAAUGUAUAGGGUAAAUAUAAUAGACUUCUCUUGAGGUUUUAAAAAUUACAUUUGUUAUUUGAAAGAAAAAAAUUAACGUUGUUGUAUGUGAUUCUCUGUAGAGGAUAUACAGUUUUUUUUUGUUGUUCUUGUUUCUGUUUUUUUAAGGUGAAGUCUCUGUCACCCAAGCUGAAGUGCAGUUCUGUGAUCAUGGCUCACUGCAGCUUCACCCUGGGUUCAGGUGAUCCUCCCACUUCAGCCUCUUCAGUAACUGGGACUACAGGCAUGUACUACCACGUCCAGCUAAUUUUUUUUUUCUUUUUUUUUUAGAGAUGGGGUCUCACUCUGUUGCCCAGGCUAAUGCCAAACUGCUAACCUCAAGAUAUUAAUACUAUACAGUAGACUAUAAGAAAUUAAGUAUUUGUAUCAUCCCUAGAGCGACACAGAUUUUUCCCUAAAAAACUACAGAUUAUUUUCAAAAGCAUUAAUAAAUUAAGGUGGAAUACUAAAAAAGAUUCAGGUAACCCAGGAACGAGAAACAGAAUAAAACAAUAGUAAACCUAAAUUUUAUUUUAUUUCAUUAAUACAGCAAUAAUUAAAUGUCAAUGAUCUAAGCUGAUUUAAAUCUAAAAACUGGAUAAGAAGCUGUGGCUUGUAAUUAAAAAUAGACCUUUAUUCACUAGACCUACAGUUUGCUUUUUUCAUAUGUUAAGAAAAGUUUAAUAUCCUGCUUCUCUAUUUCAGUUCUAGGGGCACCACUAUCAGUUAACCCUAAAGAUUUCUGUGGGUGAAACCAUUUUGAUUACCAUCUUGCUCUGCUGCCAGUUAUGGUAACCAAACUCUCUUUGUUUCUGGAUGCUAAAUCUGUCCACUUGUGCCUUAACUACAUCCUAACUCCCGUCAUCUUCAUUGAAUUUAAGGAGCCAAUUUCUUUUUUUGAGAUGGAGUUUCACUCUUGUCCAGGCUGGAGUGCAAUGGCACGAUCUUGGCUCACCGCAACCUCAGCUUCUCGGGCUUAAGUGAUUCUCCUGCCUCAGCCUCCCGAAUAGCUGGGAUUACAGGCAGGCACCACCAUGCCUGGCUAAUUUUGUAUUUUUAGUAGAGACGGGGUUUCUCCAUGUUGGUCAGGCUGGUCUCGAACUCCCAACCUUAGGUGAUCCACCCGCCUCAGCCUCCCAAAGUGCUGGGAUUACAGGCAUGAGCCACUGCACCCGGCCAGGAGCCAAUUUCAAUGGGAGUAUCCUUUACUAUCAUUCCUGACCUGUGAUAUUGGCCAUUAGAGCCUUUCAAGAAUGGUACCUCCUGCCGAUGAUUUUUUUUAAAGCCUUAAUGAAGAGAGUGUCCUCUGGAUCCUUCCAGAGAAGAUAGGAUGUGAGUGAGUAAGUUAUGUAUAAUAAUUUCACCCCAAAAUUUCUAUGUCCUUGAUACCAUUCCCUGUAUACCAAGGAAGGGUAUUCUGGCAUUUCACUUUGAUUUAAUAUAAGUAAACCCUGUGUCUGGGCAUUAGUUAACAAACCAAGUGACUACAAGUGAUAAGUAACUUUUACCAUAGACUGUCAAUUACCUUGGCAAUGGAAACAUUAUUGCUUUUUAAUCCAGUCAGAUCAGAGAACAAAUUCCAGAUUUCCAUCCUUAAGAUUCUGUGUCUCUGCUACCACUUCUGGUAGCAAAACAUGUCAGUGUGAGGUAGAGUCAAUGGAAUGUAGCCAUGAAAAAAAAAAUGCUACUACAAACAUUACAGGAAUAAGGAAUUUGAUCGAAGAAUUAGCAUUUACACAAAAUAUGGGAGGAGUUAGGGAAGUGAAAGAAUGAAAGGAGAAAGAGGAUAAAGAAAACACUAACCACAUCACCCUAAAGCCCUUAUUGCUAAAUGAGGUUAUUGUAGUGCCAGUUAAGUCCAGGUCAGCCAAGGCGUGCGUACCCCUUGGCCCCACUUGGAAAGCUGUGUGGAUAUGACUGUUGGAUUAGGGGGUUCUCAAAGCCAAAAUGGAUUUAUCAGCAAUGACCUUACUGCCUGGUACCCAGCUUUGAGAGGACCAAAAACGACGGAUGUGUCUUGCAUUCCCUGGUCCCUCUUUCUUCUUUUACCCAUAUCUAAGUUGUUUAAAGGAGAAAAAUCCUUAGGUUGAAGCCAUAUUCUCUCUAUUCUUGAAGGACCACAGACUCUACGCCCCUGUUGAAAUUUUCUGGAAGCCUAUGGGAAAGGAGGAAUGAAAAGCUUCGUGAUGUCUUUGAAUACAGGUGCCUAAGUUACUAUCGUAACUGGUCCAGUAAGGAGAAGGGGUAUCUGAAUUUCAACUUGGGGGCUGGGCAAGGUAACCAGUGAGGUGGGGAGAUAAAUAGAACUUGGUAGCUAAGACCCUUCAGGUUGGCUUGAUGAUGCAUUGUGAUCAUGGCUUCUACUUCAGAUGUGUUGCUGGAAUAGAUAUCCUUAUACUUGUAAUUCCCCUAUACACAAAUGCCAGCAAGAAUAGUCCCAUUGAGGACAUGCUAAAUGUAGAGAGGUAGUAGUAUGACAUGGAAAACACUCCCCAACUUGUCUCCCUGUCUCCUGCUUAUGUGGUACAUGGCCACUGACUACAGUAUUAACCUUUACUUGAGCCCUGUGCUUCUGGAAAACAGUGACAGUUAAGAAAUCCCUCCUUCUUGUUACAUUUCAGGAAAUGGCUUAUUGCAAAGAACCACUAGAACUCUUGGGAAUAAGACAGAGCUUCCUAUUAAGACCACCACAUCUACUCAUCUUUAAGCUGGUGAUUCUCACCAACACAUCUAAGCAUGAAAGAAAUAAAAAUUAUAAGAUAAAAAGGAAAGAAAACUCUCAGUACUUAAAGAUGAUAUAAUUACAUAGAAAAUCAAGAAGAUUCCAUGGAUAGGCUUCCCAAAAAACAAUAUGUAACAUACCAGCAACAAAUGGUAAGAAAAACACGUUGUUUUUUUUUUAAAGUACAUUUUCAGUGACAUUAAAUAAUAAGGAUUCAGGAAUACAACGAAUAUAACAAAAAUGUAAGAUAUCUAGGGAUGCGUAUAACAAAAAAAUUAUAAAGCUUCAUUUAAAACAUUUUUAAACAAAAUAAGUAGAAAGUAAUACCAUCUUUAUGGAACAGAGUCAGUAUUAUAAAUGUGUCAGUUUUCUUCAACUGGUCCAUAGACAACACAAUUUUAACUAAGAUUCCAAUUGGGAUUUCUGUGGAACUUGAUGAGUUAGGGCCAAAAGUAAUCAAGAUAUUCAUGAGGAAGGAUAACAGAAUGGCAAAACUUGCUUUAAUAAUUUGUGCAGGGAUAGACAAAUACUGUACACCAGUCUCUCAAUAGGGAGAUCAAAACCAAAUUCACACAGACAUGAAAAGUUGAUUUAUGACAGAUGAUGUUGCAGUCCCUGGGGAAAGAAUGGAAAUGGUGCUAGAAUAAUUGGUUUCUAUAUGUAUUUCUAUAUAUUUAUAUGCCAUUACAUUAAAGUCAAUGCCUAUGGAGUUUGGGAGGAGUGAUCAAAAUGUUCUGGAAUUAGAUGUGAUGUUUGCACAACUCUGUGAAUGUACUAAGAACCACUGAAUUGUAUAUUUUUAAAGCAUGGUAUGUGAAUAAUACCUCAAUAAAGCUGUUAUAAAAAAUA